GGAGUCGCGGCCUCCCCAGCUAGUGGUCGCGGGCGCGGUCGCAGGGGCAGCGGGGUGGCCGCCGCGCCAGGCGUGGAGCUGGGUCUGGCGGGCUCCGAGAGGCCCGGGAGCGGCGCGCAGAGCAGCCUCCGGCCGCCGCCGCGCAGAGCUGCCAGAGUGGACUGCACUGCUUCUCCCAGCGGGGCAGGAUGGCGGUUUCAUGUCUGGUUGGAUAAGGCCUUGCCUGCGGAAACCAGCUCCAUCCCCAGGCCCUAGCAGAGGCUCGCGUGUCCCCGUCCCCAGGUCAGGUCAGGAUGGGCACCGUGCGCCCACCUCGCCCCUCGCUCCUGCUGGUCUCCACCCGGGAGUCUUGUCUCUUCCUCCUCUUCUGCCUGCACCUGGGCGCCGCCUGCCCACAGCCCUGCCGGUGCCCUGACCACGCAGGGGCUGUGGCUGUCUUCUGCAGCUUGCGGGGCCUUCAGGAGGUCCCCGAGGACAUCCCGGCCAACACCGUGCUCCUGAAGCUCGAUGCCAACAAGAUCUCCCACCUCCCGGACGGGGCCUUCCAGCACCUGCACCGGCUCAGGGAGCUGGAUCUGUCUCACAACGCCAUCGAGGCCAUCGGCUCCGCCACCUUCGCGGGCCUGGCCGGGGGCCUGCGGCUGCUGGACCUGUCUUACAACCGCAUCCAGAGGAUCCCCAAGGACGCCCUGGGCAAACUCAGCGCCAAGAUACGCCUGUCCCACAACCCCCUGCACUGCGAGUGCGCCCUGCAGGAGGCCCUGUGGGAGCUGAAGCUGGACCCCGACUCUGUGGACGAGAUCGCCUGCCACACCUCAGUGCAGGAGGAGUUUGUGGGGAAGCCUCUGGUUCAGGCUCUGGAUGCGGGUGCCAGCCUCUGCAGCGUCCCCCACAGGACCACAGACGUGGCCAUGCUGGUCACCAUGUUCGGCUGGUUCGCCAUGGUGAUCGCCUACGUCGUGUACUAUGUGCGCCACAACCAGGAGGAUGCCCGGAGGCACCUGGAGUACCUGAAGUCUCUGCCCAGCGCCCCCGCCUCCAAGGACCCCAUCGGCCCGGGGCCCUAGCGCCUGUUCCGGCAGACCCCCGCCGGUGGCUGCUGUCACUUUUGUAGUAGGUGGUGACUGAUGCUGCUUUUGCUCUUCCCUGAGGCAGGUGUCACAGCCAUGUGUGCUCCCCACUGUUGCACUCAGGCACAGCAGCACCUCCAGGCUGGGUGGUUUUGCCACACAUCCGUGUGACGGAUGAGGAACCUGAAGCUUAGAGGAACGGAAUGACUGCCCGUGACGAUACCAUCAGGAAAUUAUCCCAGUGGAACUUCAACCCGGGCUGUCCAUCGUGACAUUCCGCCUCCUUCCACCAUGCCAGCCUCUCCCACACGGGGCCCUGCAGGCUGUGGAUAUGCACUCAGAGGACUAAGGGGGUGCUCUGCAAGCGAGAGGGUUCACCAGAGGGAGCUUGGGUGCAGGUUCACCCGCUGAAGGCGCUGAUAAGUCCUGUGCUGAGGAGCUGACUUGCCCUUGUUUACUUACAAAGUGCAUUGUAGGUAAACAUGAGCCUUGUUCCAGUGUUCGAAGUACAUUGGAACGUAAGCCCUGUUUCCAGAGCAAAGUAACAGAGACCAGGUUUUUCUAGAGAGCUAAGUGGGAUGUGUAGCUCAAACAAACUGUCCUACCCUUUUUUAUUCUCAAAUGUUUGUUUUGAGUAACCGUAGUGCCAAAAUUUCAGUUCAGUAAUGGGGUGAACAAUAUGGAGAGAGACCUGGGAAAAGUCCAGGGUAGCUUGCCCAGGGGAAGACAGCAGCCACAUACCUGGGGGCCCGCCUGCUUCCUGCCCCUCUGGGUGUGCCUGAUGCGGGAGGCCCUGCCCCAGGGCGAUCUCAGCUCACUGCAACCUUUGCCUCCCAGGCUCAAUCACUUCUGCUGCCUCAGCCUCCCUAGUAGCUGGAAUUACAGGCAUGAGCCACCACGCCUGGCUAAUUUUUGUAUUUUUAGUAGAGACCGGGUUUCACCAUGUUGGCCAGGCUGGUCUCGAACUGUUGGCCUCAAGUGAUCCGCCCGCCUCAGCCUCCCAAAGUGCUGGGAUUACAGGCGUCAGCCACCGCGCCCGGCCCUGUGCCUUGCUUUUUCUACUCACUAAGAUAUAAAACAGCUCUUUUUCCAAGGCCCGGAGUACUGGGGAUUGAUGUUUCAAGGCCAAUCAAUGGGAUGCUUCGUUUUCUCCAGCAACAGGAACUCUCUCUUUUCACCUUUGCUGCCAGGAAUCUCAGAGAUAAUUUAGUGCUCAAUUUACUAACCUUACUUCACAUUCAGGUUAGAUGUUACCUCCACCUAUAUGAUAGUAAUUCCUAAUUUUAUUUUUUAUUGUCCUUUUUAUGAGUGUUUAUAUUUUAAAGUACUUUGAGUAUUUUUGGGGGGGGUGUAAAUGAGUGAUCAGUGUACAUUGUGUGUGGACUGAAGUGUAGGUAUGUAGAGAUGCUUCGCCAAACAGAUGCUUAAAAAUGAAUGGAAGUUGAGGGUGGUUUCUCUUUGGAAAGUAUCAGGUGACUUGGAAGGUGAGAGCCUGUCCAGGGUGUGUGCACUGGUUCUGAGGUACCCCGUGUGUGCAGUGUGAGUCACGGGGGUGUCUGUGUUGUGAGGUGCUUGGUAGGCUUUGCUCUGCCCACAGUGCAGACGCGGGGUGGGUGAGGGGCCAGGCCCAGUGUAUGAGUGGAGGCAGCCCCAGGCUCCGCCUGCUUCCCUCACGCCACGCUGCCUGAGUGUCGCCAUGCUCGGAGGACAGAGACCUCCACGGAAACUGGCAGCGCCACUCACCCUUCCAGUGAGAGCUAGAACCAAGUGCCAGCCCCCGGGGGUGCACCCGUGCUGGUGUGGGGCCACGUGGUCCUUGUGGUCCAGGCAGGGCCAGCAUGUGGCGGGGUGUCCAGCUCCACUGUUUGGAGGAAGUGGGCGCUGACACAGCAGAGUGCCCUGGGCCCGUGGGGAUUUCCUUCCAGAGGACACGUGGCUGAAAGCAUAGGAUAAGGAUGUAUAGGUGAAUGACUGGUGCCAUCCCUGGCUGUCUGAUAGAUGCAGGUAGGGCAGGUGAACUGUUGCUGGCCUGGCCAGCAGGCCUAGGGUCACAUGGUGAUUGGCGUCCUCCUGCCACCCCUUCUCCAUGCCAGGGUGCCUGUGGUGGGUUUGCCCAGCACGCAUGACCCCAGGUCCCAAGGAGAGUGUGAACUGAGGCCUGGGUGGUGAAGGCAGGGCCUCUCCUCAGCCCUGUGUCCUGUGGGUGCCAGCCAGUCCCAUCUCGCAUUUUGGGGUGCCCUUUCCCUGCUGCCAGGGGACUCUUCAUUUGUCCUUACCCUAGAAUCAGCCCAGACACUGGACAUCACCCAGACGUGGCCCUUCAGGAGGUGCACAGGGCAGGGGCAGGCCCGUCCCUCCCUGCCCCAAUUUGCUGGGCUGCCUCAGCCCAGGGUCUGGCCUUCUCCUUGGUGAAGGUCUGCUGGGCCCCUGUCCACCUCCUGCUGGGAGGAGGAGAUGGGGAGAGGACCAGGAGGACACCGGAGGCCCUGUCCCCUGCACUGUGAGCUCAGUCAGGUCCAUGAGCUGCCCACCGUCCUGGCCUUACUGUGCCCCCUGCCCCACCAACAUAGGUGAAAGCACCUCCCCUCUAAGGAAGACCAUAGAGACCCCAACACUGUGGGACCCCAAAGCUCCUUCAUGCUCACUGGAGCUCCCACCGUGGGUGCUUGCAAGUCCUCAGCGCUCCCGGGGUACAGCCCUCCCCUUCCUGCCCUCUAAUGUCCUCCCCUCCCUUGCCCUUCCCUCCACUUCCUUUCUCUGCCGUCCCCUCCUCUCCCAUCUUGUGACCUCUUUACUGGCGGGGCCUGGAGCCCAUGAUGGACACUUGCGGAAGGAGGGGUGGCGGAGCACCCCUGAGAUGACAUCGCUGCCUGCCCCAGAGCACCCCGCCUCUCCCUGUGACUCAGUUCUUUGCAGCCCAGAUGUGAGCAUGUGCACCCUGGGACCUGCUGCCCGUUGGGAUGCCCAGGCCAAAUCAGCCCCUCUGCCUCCAUGCUGCACUGAUUGCAAGAGUUUCCCACAUCUGCAGAGGCCGUGGGCUCAGCCCCACACCAGCCAGGCCACCAGUGUUGAUAGCGGUGAGGCGGGGACAAAGGGAAUGUCUCAGUUCACAGUGUGGACAUGGUGGAGGUCUCGGCCUUGCGAGACAAGGCAGGGGGAGGGGAUAGGAAAUUGGGGGUAUUCUGUGACUCCUGGGCCACCGGGGAGCCAGAAUCUUCCAGCCAGACUGGAUGGGCAGGGCUUAGCUUCCUGAUGCCGCCCAUUCACCACUUUCACCCCGGGAACCUACCUGGGCAUCAUGGGAGGCAGAGCCUGAACCCCAACCCAACCCUAACUCUAAUGCUAACCCCUAAACCAUCCCCCACCCUAACCCAAUCCUCGCCCUAACCCUAAUGCUAACCCCUGACCCGACCCAAUCCUAACCCUGAUGCUAACCCCUGACUCAACUCUCACCCUAACCCUGAUGCUAACCCCUGACCCAAUCCUCACCCUAACCCUGAUACUAACCCUUAACCUAACCCAACCCAGCCCUAACUCCAACUCUAAAGCUAACUCCUAACCCUAGGAGAGGAGCCCAGGCCGGGCCCUCUCCCUGCUGGUUUCCUGUUGGGCUUUGGAGCCCCAGAUGCCUGCCCAGAGGCUUCCUUGUGCGGGGUGGGGUCCAGCAGUGGGGGAUGGGCCCAGAGCUGGUAUAGCCACCAGCAGAGCCAUCCUGAUCCACAGGACCAUCCCUGGUGGGGUGGGGCCCCCUGGGGCAGGAAGGCCACUGAGGCCAGGGAGACUCCCAGGCCCACUCACGGCGCAGGCCCCACAGGAGCUGGCUGGAGGCUAUGGGUGCGGGGCGUGGGCCUGCCGGGGGUUGCGUGACAGGCAGUGGGGAGUGGGUUGUGCUGGCAGCUGUGGGUGAGUGAGGAGGCUCCUCUCAUGAAGGGCCCUGGGGAAGUGGAAUCUGGCCCUGAGAGACCCCCGGCCUCCUCUGCAGGGGCUGCUGGCAGGAGGGGAACCGGGGACCACCUCCCGCCACAGAGCCUGGGGCCCCCAGCCUUGCCUACAGGGAGGGUAGAUGAGAGUGUAAACUGCAUAUGAGGUUGGGCUAAACCUGGACAUGUGUUUCAUAACCAAAGCAGCCAGGAAUCUCCGGCUCUGCCCAGUGAUCAUCUGGGCAGGACAUGGGGACGAGUGUCCAGGCUGAAGUCAGGGCCCGGCCAGCAGAGGGCCAUUUUGUAUUGAGCUCCACAGCUGGUCACAUUCUGUGGAAUGUGCAGACGUGCACGGCCCAUCAGACAGGGUCUGGAGUGGGGCUGCCGUCUUGGGCAGCUCCUCCCGGGUGUCUGCAAAAUGCAGAGGUCACCAGAGCCAAGGCAGCAAGGCAAGGAGCCCGGCUUCUAAGGAACUCUGAGCAGGUGUGGUCCAUGGCUGGGAGGCAGCUGGCCCCACAGCACAUAGCACGGAGGGCGGCGCGGAGUCCUGGACGCUCUUGGCAGGUCCCCUCAUGGAGGAUGUGGGGGAUUGGCUUAGGCCUGGUCUGGCUGGCCUUCCUGGACCGCAGUGGCCAGGAGCUGAAAACCGUGACCCCAGUCUCCCUGCAGCUGUUCUUGAUGGGAUUUCUGUUCGCCAGUCAGAUGCAUUUGCACAGGACUUGGAUCCUGAACUGUGUAACCUGGAGAGGCAGGUGUGAGCGGGCCAUGCUGCUGGCCCAGCCUGUGCCGGUGUCUGUUUCUGUUGUCUCUCGGCCCUUCUGUGAGCCCUCAGUAAAGCUCUUCGUGCUUCAGUCA